GUCGGCUUCCGGAAGCUCAUCUCAAAAUGCUGAACUGCUCUUUGGAAGUCGCCGGUGCUGUUGUAGUUGGAGUCUGUUCACGGGCCUGAGCUUCGAGGCCAGGCUCCCGGGUGUCGUUAAUGUUCGGGGCCGCCGGGCGCCAACCGAUCGGAGCUCCAGCAGCCGGGAACAGCUGGCAUUUCAGUAGAACCAUGGAGGAGCUGGUUCAUGACCUUGUCUCAGCAUUGGAAGAGAGCUCAGAGCAAGCUCGAGGUGGAUUUGCUGAAACAGGAGACCAUUCUCGAAGUAUAUCUUGCCCUCUGAAACGCCAGGCAAGGAAAAGGAGAGGGAGAAAACGGAGGUCGUAUAAUGUGCAUCACCCGUGGGAGACUGGUCACUGCUUAAGUGAAGGCUCUGAUUCUAGUUUAGAAGAACCAAGCAAGGACUAUAGAGAGAAUCACAAUAAUAAUAAAAAAGAUCACAGUGACUCUGAUGACCAAAUGUUAGUAGCAAAGCGCAGGCCGUCAUCAAACUUAAAUAAUAAUGUUCGAGGGAAAAGACCUCUAUGGCAUGAGUCUGAUUUUGCUGUGGACAAUGUUGGGAAUAGAACUCUGCGCAGGAGGAGAAAGGUAAAACGCAUGGCAGUAGAUCUCCCACAGGACAUCUCUAACAAACGGACAAUGACCCAGCCACCUGAGGGUUGUAGAGAUCAGGACAUGGACAGUGAUAGAGCCUACCAGUAUCAAGAAUUUACCAAGAACAAAGUCAAAAAAAGAAAGUUGAAAAUAAUCAGACAAGGACCAAAAAUCCAAGAUGAAGGAGUAGUUUUAGAAAGUGAGGAAACGAACCAGACCAAUAAGGACAAAAUGGAAUGUGAAGAGCAAAAAGUCUCAGAUGAGCUCAUGAGUGAAAGUGAUUCCAGCAGUCUCAGCAGCACUGAUGCUGGAUUGUUUACCAAUGAUGAGGGAAGACAAGGUGAUGAUGAACAGAGUGACUGGUUCUACGAAAAGGAAUCAGGUGGAGCAUGUGGUAUCACUGGAGUUGUGCCCUGGUGGGAAAAGGAAGAUCCUACUGAGCUAGACAAAAAUGUACCAGAUCCUGUCUUUGAAAGUAUCUUAACUGGUUCUUUUCCCCUUAUGUCACACCCAAGCAGAAGAGGUUUCCAAGCUAGACUCAGUCGCCUUCAUGGAAUGUCUUCAAAGAAUAUUAAAAAAUCUGGAGGGACUCCAACUUCAAUGGUACCCAUUCCUGGCCCAGUGGGUAACAAGAGAAUGGUUCAUUUUUCCCCGGAUUCUCAUCACCAUGACCAUUGGUUUAGCCCUGGGGCUAGGACAGAGCAUGACCAGCAUCAGCUUCUGAGAGAUAAUCGAGCUGAAAGAGGACACAAGAAAAAUUGUUCUGUGAGAACAGCCAGCAGGCAAACAAGCAUGCAUUUAGGAUCCUUAUGCACGGGAGAUAUCAAACGGAGAAGAAAAGCUGCACCUUUGCCUGGACCUACUACUGCAGGAACAUGUAGCCACAUUUUGGAUGAAACACAUGUCAUCAGUCUUGCAAUUCAGAUCUUUCAUAAGGCAGGAUUUGUAGGUGAAAAUGCCCAGCCAAUCCUAGAAAAUAAUAUUGGAAACCGAAUGCUUCAGAAUAUGGGCUGGACGCCUGGGUCAGGCCUUGGACGAGAUGGCAAGGGGAUCUCUGAGCCAAUUCAAGCCAUGCAGAGGCCAAAGGGAUUAGGACUUGGAUUUCCUCUACCAAAAAGUACUUCCGCAACUACUACCCCCAAUGCAGGAAAAUCCGCCUAAGAAAAGCAAAGAAGAAAUGUUUUACAGACUUUAUUCACUAUGUCCCAUUGUUCUAAAAUGAUAACAUGACUUCUGUUUUUGAAGCAAAAAUCUACAUUGCCUCAAACACAUCACUCUAGCUUCCUUACUGCAUACAGUCCUGCCAUAGUGAGAGAAAUGGGAUUUCAUCACAAUUCAUGGUGCUAAAAUGAAAACCUCUGCACUUUAAUUUUUUUCAGUAAUUUCCAGCUAUUUCUAGGUAUAAAGAGCAGCUCGUUUCUCUUAUUUAUUUUAGUCUCAUGUGUCAAUACUUUCCGAUGCUUUGCUUAAUUCAUGUAUGUGUGCAGUGCUGCAAUGCCCAGACAAACGUGAGCACACCCACCAGUUUCUAAAAUGGAAUAGACAGGAAAAGAUUGUGUUUUAUAUCAUCCCUAUCUAUUGUAACCCAAAAGACCUACCAUCGCAUCAGUGAAGUCCGAACACAUCUUUGUUUGAAAGGCUUGUCAAUUUCAUAUUCCUUGAAUUGGCUUCUUGGUGAGGAUUUUCUGACAGAGUGAUACCCAUCAAUUUUCUAUCCUUAGACAAUGUAGUGUGAAGUUCACAGUUGACAAACAACAAUUAAUGUUUCCCUUGGAUGUUUUGACAAAAAUAAACCUCAUCGUUGUUAUCACCAGAGUGCCCUCUACCUUACUUUAAUGCAGAUUUUAUAAAUUUUACCUCAUUUAGAACAUAAAAUAAUUAUUGAAAGAAAAAUGUAUUUUUUAAAUUCACCGUGAUUGAACUGUAAAUUCUAUUAAUCCAGAUGUACUUCUACCUCUGUUUUCCCAAAGAUUGAUAUUAUUUUUAAGAUCAACUCAAGUGUAGUAAACGGAUUUAAAAUUUUAAUCAUUGGAGUAAUUUAUUACAAUAUUGAAUCAAUUUACAUGAAAAGUUAAAUGGCUCUCCCAGAACUCAGAUUUCUGGCAAUGACCCAACCCAUUUAGAAGGUGAACAAAAGAAGUAAAUGGUACUGAUUUGCCCUUUCUAGGACCCAAGAUGUUACUUUAAAACCUAGCAAAAGAGGUCGUUUGUAUUACGUGCCUAGUAUUGAGCUGUUUCUGAGUCAUUUGCUUCAUAGUAUCAGAAAUUCUAAAUUGCUUUUAGUUUAGAAGAUCUUUAUUUAUUAUCUUCAUUAUUAACAACUUAUUAUGAUGAUGAUUAUUAUCAUUCUAUUUAUAAUGGCCUUUGCUGGUUGAGUAAAGACUGAGAUAACACAUGUGAAUCACCUUUCUAAUGGGUUUUUAAAAUCUUGUCACUUUCCAAAAGAGUUUUUUUGUUUCUUUUUUUUUUUUUUUUUUUUUGACAGAGUCUGCCUCUGUCGCCCAGGCUGGAGUGCAGUGGCGCACUCUCGGCUCACUGCAGCCUCCCCCUCCUGGGUUCAAGUGAUUGUUCUGCCUCAGCCUCCCAAAUAGCAGGGAUUACAGGCACCCACGACCAUACCCGGAUAAUUUUUGUAUUUUUAGUAUAGACGGAGUUUCACCAUGUUGGCCAGGCUGGUCUCGAACUCCUGACCUCAAGUGAUCCGCCCACCUUGGCCUCCCAAAGAGCUGGGAUUACAGGCAUGAACCACAGCGCCCAGCCCCCAGAAGAGUUUUUAAAAGGUGUUAAAGGAGGUUUAUGCACGUAACAGACCUUUCUCAGGUGGUCCCCUAAAAAAAAUCCUGCCAACUAGGGAGGGGAAGUCCAACCUGCUAUUUGAAAGCCUUCACGGUUUGCCAAAUGUACAUUUCUUGAGAAUUAUCUUCUUUCCCAGGGAUAUUGUACCUAGAGGACAGGUUGGUUAGGGAACUAUGGACGACCAGAAGAGAUGUUCUUUUGAAGCAUUCUUACUGGAUAAAGUAACCCCAUGGUAUCAUUACUUUCUACAAGUUUUUUACUUACAAAUUUGCCAUUUUUUUAACUGAUAUUUUCUAAAUGCUCAUUCUGUCUAUGUAGCCGGGGGGAGAUUAUAUACAAGUUUUAAAACUUCUUUGUGAUAGUGUAUUGUGCUCUGGGGUCUAUUCAAAAUUUGGUGUUUGAGGUUUUGUUAAUUUGAUUGCCUGGAGAUCUGCUAAAAUCCUAGAAUCUCAAAAAGCCAAGUUUGAAGCCACUGAGAGCAAACAAUGAGGUCAUUGUUAGCCUGGUUCCACACUCCUGAGGACUUGGCUGUUCUUUUUCACCUUAUUAUGUUCUAAUGGAAGUAAAAACCCUCAUAGUGAAGAAGAGCAGUAUAUACACCAGACUAGUGUAUAGGAACUUCUUCAUUAAAUAUUGCAGUCCUUAUGAGUGCUCUUUAUUGUUGCUGUUCUGGACAGGUACAAAUCUUCUGAAGCAACUUCUGUGGGAUGUUAACUUAGCUUCUCUAACACCUAAAAAAAUUCUUCUUUGUAUUUUCAGCUAAUAGAAGACAGUUCUUCUUCAUCUUGACACCUAGAGCCCUCUAUGUGAUUCACAGAGGACUUAAAAUACUUCUUACUCUGUUGAAGUGUUUAAUUGUACAGAAUAUAUGUACUCUACAGUAUAUGUGAAUCAGCACUCAAAGCAGAGAAGUGAUAACAUCCCAAGCUUCCCCCAUACUUCUACUGACAUGCCCUCAGUCUUUAAGAAAACUCAGUACAGACCUGAUGUUCUGGUUGUACCUGAACUUAAUUGGAGAAACAAACGCAAUUAAAAUACGAAUUUUUUAGUGCAAAUCAAAUGUCUUUCACCAUCUGAAGCCCACUAAUUUGUCUUUUAUAUAUAGUUAAUUUUUUGCCAGUUACAACGUCCAUAGAACCCCAAGAUUUAGAAUGUAUCAUUUAUAUUUCCUCUAAAAGGUAGUAAGAUAUUUCUUCUGCUGUUUUGUGAAGCCACUCUUCUACAGUAUCUGUAGCCUUAUAGCAAAUUAAUUGGUUGUACUAAAAAUUUUAGAGACUGCAUAGGUCUCCCUUUUCUAUCCUAAUUACCUGCAAUAGCCUAGAGACGCUGAGCAUGAUUACAUUAGCAACUUGACUGUUUAAAAAAUUUGUUAUACUUGAUAAUGACCAGACUGUGUGCUGGAGUCAUUUGUUUCCUUCUUUUCUGCUCCCCGAAUACACUAUUUAAUUUGGUUACUUUUAUUUUUAAACUAUAUGGCACCCUUUUAAAUAAACAUUCAUUGCUAAUUAAAAUCUGCCAAUAAAUUGGUCUCAGCAUUUAAAUACCAUAUAUUUUAUAACUCAUACUGUGGCUAUCAAACAGAAGUUAACACAGUAGGGGUAAAGAUAUACAUAAUGUGUACCUAUAGGUGUAUUUAUAAUGCCUGUGUGCAGUAUACAGACAUAAUUACAAAAUACUGCAUUUUAUUAAUGUUUAUUUUAAUAUUGAGAAUUGGCAUUCUUGUAAAUUGAACUGACAAUUGCUUCUAUUCAGUACACUUUAUUUUGAGCAGAUAUUUCCGAAAAGAGAAAAAAUCACUGUUGACAUGCUUUUUAAAACUGUUUUCACCUGUAUUUUGUCUUUCAAAAAGAAAAGUGAUCUAAGUUGGCAUUGUAAAGAAAUUGUUAGCAAAGAAUAUUUUUUUUUAUUUUUUCUUUUGGUAGAAAGUCAUGUUAAUAGUACAACAAAGAAUCAAAGAAUAAAACAUAAUGUUUAAGAACAUUAUUUAUAAGUAGUCAUUGUCUUUGUGCUUUAAAUGUUUCCCUUUUACCUUAGAGUUAUUUUUUAAAAGUUGAAAGUACUUUAAAAAUUGGUUUAAAUGAGUACCCAUUGACAAUUAUCAUUUAAUAGUGCAGUUAAGUUCAGCGAAAAAUUUCAAUAUCUCAAAAAAAUUAGAGAAAAAUAUUGGUAAAUGUAUUUGAUUCACAAAUGUAUUCAUAGCCGAUUGUGAGCUGCUCUACCACAUUUUCCUGUUUUUAUUGUUUCUGUGAAGCUUGAUUAGACUAACUUGCUUAAGGUCUCUUUCCCCUCAAGGAUUCUGUGAUUCUAAUGUAACAAGGUACACACGCUCUCUCUGACCACUUAAAGUAUCAGAGUUCAAAUCUGUUACAAUCACUCCAUUUCCUUUUGGAAAGUUGUGCCUCUCAUAAAGCUGCUUGGACAUUUUAAGUGUUUUGUAAUAUGCAUUGAAGUGUUGAGUUUUGUUUGCUGUAAGAGGCAUUUCACUAUGUUGAUUAAACUUAUCUUUUCUCCCAAAAAA